GUGCGAGGCAGCGGGGCUGAGCUAAGCCGAGCCCACGUGUGACGGCUCUCGCCGCUGCCCCGGCUCCGCCGCUCGCAGAGAGAUUCGGAGGAGCCCGGGCGGGGGGGAGGAGGAGGGGGAGGAGGGAGCGGAGAUCUCGGGGCUCGGAGCCGGCCGCCGCUCCGCUCCGAUCGCUGUGGGGCUUGGUUUUUUGGGGGUGGGGGGGCGGGGGGGCUCAGAUAUGGAGGCAAAUGGGAGCCAAGGCACCUCGGGCAGCGCCAACGACUCCCAGCACGACCCCGGUAAAAUGUUUAUCGGUGGACUGAGCUGGCAGACCUCACCAGAUAGCCUUAGAGACUAUUUUAGCAAAUUUGGAGAAAUUAGAGAAUGUAUGGUCAUGAGAGAUCCCACUACGAAACGCUCCAGAGGCUUCGGUUUCGUCACGUUCGCAGACCCAGCAAGUGUAGAUAAAGUAUUAGGUCAGCCCCACCAUGAGUUAGAUUCCAAGACGAUUGACCCCAAAGUUGCAUUUCCUCGUCGAGCGCAACCCAAGAUGGUCACAAGAACAAAGAAAAUAUUUGUAGGCGGGUUAUCUGCGAACACAGUAGUGGAAGAUGUAAAGCAAUAUUUCGAGCAGUUUGGCAAGGUGGAAGAUGCAAUGCUGAUGUUUGAUAAAACUACCAACAGGCACAGAGGGUUUGGCUUUGUCACUUUUGAGAAUGAAGAUGUUGUGGAGAAAGUCUGUGAGAUUCAUUUCCAUGAAAUCAAUAAUAAAAUGGUAGAAUGUAAGAAAGCUCAGCCGAAAGAAGUCAUGUUCCCACCUGGGACAAGAGGCCGGGCCCGGGGACUGCCUUACACCAUGGACGCGUUCAUGCUUGGCAUGGGGAUGCUGGGAUAUCCCAACUUCGUGGCGACCUAUGGCCGUGGCUACCCCGGAUUUGCUCCAAGCUAUGGCUAUCAGUUCCCAGGCUUCCCAGCAGCGGCUUAUGGACCAGUGGCAGCAGCGGCGGUGGCGGCAGCAAGAGGAUCAGGAUCUGCACACCUCCUCUCAAACACUCUUCUGAGCACGCUCAGCGGGAAGGUUUGUCCACACCUAUUAAUCCUCUCUCAGUGUCCAGCUUCCUGUUAGUACCAGCUGGUUUGCAUGUUUUUGCUUGUUCAGAUGAAACAGUUCAAGAAACAAACUCAUAUCCAACUCUCAAGAAAUGUCUUUUUUUGUACACUUUCGUUUUUGAUUUUUUUUAUUAGUUACAACUCCAAAACACCUGUUGUCCAGUAAAACAUUUCACACCUCCCCUGCCUGUUCUUAGAUUGUAUGUAUCUGUGGGACUGAACUAAAUGCAUGCACCGUAGUAGAUGUACUGGUAGCCGUAGCUGUAGUUGUAGUACAUGCAUUGUUGAGUUGAUAUUACAGGGUCUUUGACGGCUCGGCACAGCACGGCCGUCUGAAGGAUAGUGCGGGGACCAGGAAGAGAAGGGGCUCCAUAUUUUCAAUGUUUCCAAGGGGCUUGGAUCCAUGUUCUCACCAUCAGCCACCACCACCUCCCCUCACACUCCCCGUUCCCCCAGUCCAGAACUGGGUCACCACCCUCAGCUCUAGCCUUCCUCACUGAGGUCUCUGUUGAUAUCGUCCAAUUAUAGUGCAAAAAUGGAGCCAGGAUUGGAAGGAGUCUUAAAGGUCUUCCUUGUUCUUGUCUUUCUCAUACUAUUCUUGAACAGAGCAGAUCUUUUUUUAUUUCUUAAGGCCUACCAGCAAGACUCCUUCAAGCCCUUCUACUCCUUGAGUCCUUUGGCAGGUCACAGCCAGCCCUUCAGGGAUACGGGUCUAUGUGGCAGUCCUGUCUAUAUGGAUUACUUCUUGGGGUGGAGGGGAAAUGAGACAUGGUAAGGAAGGGAUUGAGAUCUUGAGAUCCUUGGUCUGCAGACAGGGAAUGCACUUGGCCCUAGUGAAUCAUUGCUAUUUGUUCUUAGGGUUGGUGAAGGUUAAGUAGGGUGAGAGUGGUGACAUUCUUAGCAUGGAGGUGACUGGCACAGUUUCGUGGAGACAGAAAGGGAGGUCGGCUUGGAACAUCCAAGAGGAACCACCCCUAGUUUCCUCCAGUUCCCCAGGAAGGCUCCCUAGAGGGGAAAGGAGCAGUCCUGCAGCCUGUGCCCUUAGAACAGGAGCACGUGCUGCCAGUCAUCUUUGGACAUGCCAUCUUCCCUACAUUUGUGGUGACAAGCCAUAAGGGAGUGCCAGAGGUCUCUCAGAGCUUCUGGAGGUGUCCCUACUCUUUACGUGUUGAUGCUGAGUGAGUAGUGCCUGCCUCCUGGAACCUGCUCUUUAAGUCAGGAUGUGGUGGCUCUGCCCAGUGCUGCAAGAACAUUGAUGGAACACAGGUGGGAUCUGAACCUUCAGGGUGCAAGUUAUCUACUGUGGGAGACAGAAGCCCAGGAAAACGUCGGAGUCCAUAAAGUCCCCUGAGAGAAUGCGUAGAGAUAGAGCAAAAUGGUAGCGCUGUGGAAAGAAUGUACCAUGCUGUGGAAAUUGGUGGCAGAAUCGGAAUGAACAAGGAUUGAAUGUGAGUAAGGCCAGUCUGCCACCAAACAGGAUGAGGGUGCCAAGGCCCAGGAAGAUAAAUCUGGAAGGAGCUGUUCUUCUAGCUUGGCCUGCAUGGGGGUGCGGGUGAGGGAGGUACACAGGGAGAUGGCUGGAACUGUCAGGCUUCAGGGCUGCUGAAGCUGCAAAUUGGCCCGAGGCUGGGGAGUAAGAGAAGAGGGUAGGGACAGAAGGCAGAGAGAGCAGAAAAUCCCCUCCCACUGGCCUAAAUCCCAGGUCUGGUUCUGCUAGGAAAAUGGCUUUGCUGCCCUGUGGCUGGAAAUUCUAAGAGCUCCAGUUCCAGUUGGUAAAAUGAGCAAAAGUAAAAUGCAAGUCAGGGGAUGGAAUAAAUAGUUUAACUUGAACCAGAAGAGAAAAUGCUUUAGGGAGGAGAAUAGAUCUCAAGAAGUAGAUAUGCCCAUCCCAAUCCCCCUUCAAGAUGUUUUCUGUGUCCCCACUGCUAGCCUCUGCCUUAUAUAUGUUAGGGGCUGGGGGACAUGAAAGAUAGUGUCCCACAUACACUCUUCCACUUGCUGGAGGGAUCCUGGAGCUAUUUGGGUCAGUUGUACCAUAAGCUUUAGGGUUCCCAGGUAUUGCUUUCAACAUGUAUUUAUUAAGGAUUUGUUUUGUACCAAGCACCAAGGAAUAUAAAGGCAGAUGGCAUUUCUAGCCUUCAGUGGCCUGAGACUCUGGUCCUGUCCUCUGAAAGUCCGUGUUUCCCACAAUGCACUGUUUCUGGCCUCAGAAUGACCACUGUCAGCUUCAUUUAAAAAAGGAAAAUGGAUCAAUGUGUGCCUUCAUUUCUGAAGAUGGCUUUCCUGUGCUUCAUGAGCAAGAUCUGAUGGGGGGCGGAGCGGGGGAUGCAGUGCCUCCAUCUCUGCUUCCUCACCCAGCCUCCUGUGCUAGCAGCAAGCAUCCUCUGGGGGCUGUGGACCCAAGAUGGUCCAUUUGUGGGUAAGGUCAUGGGGACACCCUUGUGCUAAGACAAAGCCACAUCUGUGGCCAUAGAAUACAGCCAGUAGUGGCCCAGGGGGAGAACAAAUCUCUGACCCACUAGGGCCAGCCACCACAACCAGACUUACCAAAGGAUCUUACCUGAACACACAUCUCUCAGUCUACUGCCAUGUGUUCUGGGGAUGGAUACCUCGUUUCCCAGUUUGUCAUUAAAAUGUUCAUUUCUGGGAGAGCCAGGACUUUCACCAUAAAGAGUCCAGCAUUGGAUUUCAGUAACCCCAGUGAAUUUAUAAUAAUGCUGACAGCUGCCCGCUGCUGACCUCAGCUUCAUUCAUUUUCCAAGGGCUUUCAGACCAAACCUGUUGAGGAUAAAAUACAUCAGCUCUAAUCAAUAAUUUUGUAAUAGAAAUACUGUGCACUUGAUAAAUCAACUCUAGUGCAAUUAGUGACUAGCCUUGAAGCCCAGACCUAAGUAUAAGUUAAUCCUAAAGUGAAUGGAGUGGGGGAAUGUUAAUGGUCUUUCAAAUCAGUGGAAUUAUUUUCAGUGGUUGACACAUCUCUGCCUGCCCCCUGAGCUGGUUGGUCGUUGCUCUUGUGUGGGCUCAGGAGCUCAGGCCCAGCUGUCUGGAGCAGGGGUGGAAAGUGUGGUGGUGUCCUUCAUAGCUCCAUAAGGGCGCGCAGAGCACAACAGAGAGGGGUCUAGAGACCCGCUCCUUGCACCCUGGGCUGGGUGGGGGCACUGCAGGGUCUAGGAGGCCCCUAAAGCUGAUCAACCUGCAGGUUGGUGAGAACCAUCCAAGGAGCAUGUGCCCGGGUGUAUCAUUCAUGGUUGCUUGUGUUUUGCAGAGGUUUUUUUUUUAUUUGGUUGGUUGGUUGGUUGGUUGGUUUGUUGUUGUUGUUUUGAGACAGACUCUCACAUGUUGCCCAGGCUGGAAUGAAGUGCAGUCUUGAACUCCUGAGCUCAAGUGAACCUCUUUCCUCAGCCUCCCAAGUAGUUGGAAAUGUAGGUUCAUACUACCAUGCCCGGCUUUGGUUUUUUUGUGUGUUUUUUGUUUUUUCUUUUUUUGUUUGUUUGUUUUUGGUAGAGACAGGGUCUCACUAUAUUGCUCAAGCUGGUCUCAAACUCCUGGCCUGAAAUGAUCCUCCUACCUUGACCUCCCAAAACACUGGAAUUACAGGUGUGAGCCACUGUGCCUGGCCUCUGCAGAGUUUUGACUUUCAGAUAUACACCGUGAUGUAUAUUACCAUAGCCACCCUGGGAGACGGUCAGGAAGGCAGAAGUUUGUGGCCUGGUUUACAAGCAUGUUUUUGUUUUGUUUUUGUGAGAAAGCUGGGCUACAGAAUGGCCAUGUGACUUAUUUAAAAUCACACACCUGGUUACCGGAGAGCAAGGCUUUGGUUAAAGGUGAAGAACCCUGGACUUGAACCCAGGUCUCUGGCCUCCUUAAGUAGCCCUCUGGAGAAGCCGUGUUUUUUAUGAGGGACACACCUGCCCCCCAGGACACCGGGCACAAGCAGGAAUAAAGACCAUGUAGGAAAAAUAAUAAAAUAAAAUAAAAGCCCAUGUAGGGACAGCCCAAGUAGCCUCAGCUUCUAGCUCUAUAUAGGCCAAGCGCUCAGUCUCUGGCCUAAAACCUCAUAGUCUGAUCUUUCAGAUGUAGAUUUCAGAACUGGACCUACGGGACAUCUGCCAUGGAGUUGAAUGUGGCAGAUAUUUAUUAAGUAUAUAACAAUAGUAAUUAUUGUUAUAUGUGGUAGGUACUGUCCUAAGCCUGAUUCAAGGGUGCUUUUGACUGUAUCAGAAACCUCCCAACUCUGAUUAAACACUAUAGGUUAAUGUUACAGGGAAUUAAAUAUUAUGGGGGAUUUAUUGGCUGACAUCCUGGAAGCUCCAUAGAAGAGUGGGCUUCGUGCCUGGCUUGUUCAGGGAUCCUUUUUCUGCAAUUCUCUUAGCUUCGCCCUCCUUCUCAUUUCAAUACUGUCUUUAUAUUGGUUUUCCUCAUGGUGGCAAAAUGAUUGCAGCAGUUUCUGGCAUCAUACCGUCCUGUCCAGAAGAGGGGAGUCAGAUGGUCUGGAAUGCUAGGAAGAGUCCAGAGCUUUGUGCUGCUUGGCUAAGGCUGGGGUUACAAAACCAGUCACUGAGGGUGGGAUCCACCCCCUCUAAACCGAAUGGCUCUUUACACGGUGGUGUAAGGAUGGGUUCCCAAAGGAAAACCUGCAUGCUGAUAAGAGGGGAAAAGGAAGAAUGAUGCCAGAGAGACAACCAGUGGAUGCCCACCACAGCCCUGGAAGUUCCUGGAAGUUCAUGGAUAAAUACUAAGCAGUCUCCACGCCAUUGAAGAUCUCCCAACCUAGUGUGGAAACUAAUGGGUAAUUACAAUAGGAUGCCAUAAGCCCGGUAACAUAAGCCUAUCCAAUGAACAGAAGUAGCACAGAGGAGGAAGUGAUCAGCUUUGUCUGGGAAGUCAGGGAAUGUUUCACAGGGGAGUGAAUAUUUCCACUUUUAAAGGACAAAUAGGAGCUCCCCAGGGGGCCGGGGAACAUCAUGGGCAAAGCCACCAGACCUCGGGACAAUGGAGUGAGGUGGAGGCCCUGCUUUAUUCUGGCUGGAGAAUAAAAUGCAACAGGGGAGUAACUGUAGGUAAAGCCAGAGAGCUGGGCAGAAUCAGAGCAGGGGACCCUUGGUACUACGCUAAGGAGACUGGAUUUACAUGGGCAGGGCCUGUGAGAUCAUGGGAGGCCUGAAACUAGGAACUGACAUCAGAUUUGUAUGUUAGACAAGCUUUGACAACAUUGUCCAGGAUGGAUUCAAGACGCAGGACUGAGGUGGGAGGACAAGUUACAGAUAAUUCGUGUACAUUGUAAACACUCCAUAGAUGUUAGUAUAUAGCUGCUCAAGAAGCAGUAGGCCUUUUGCUCUUAUCCAUAAGACGAUUAACUCUGGACUCAACAUCAUGCUAGGGGCUGGGGUGGGCUGCAGAAUAAGUCCAUGGCAUGGUCCUUGCCUUUAGCCGACUUCCAGUCCUCUGGGGAGGACAAAAGUACACAACCGAUGUGAGAGCUAGCCUUUAAUAAGGAUAGAUUCCUACAAGGUCAGAGAGUACCCAGAAGGCAGGAAGCUUAGUGGAGGAGGCAAGACAUGACACAGGGCCUGGAGAAUUUGGAGUGGGAAGCUGUCUGCUAGGCAGGGAAUAUGGGCUUGAAGAGAUAGAGACAGUCAAGGUUCUGGGAGAUCUUGAAAGCCAUGUUGAUAUAGUCACAGGAGAGGGAGGUUCGUAUUCUUCAUGCAAGUGGCGCUCAGUAAGGACAGAACCAUCUAAAGAAGAUAAGCCUGGCUGUAGCUCCACAAAGAACAGCCUGACCCCUAAUCCUGGGGUCUGGGGCUGGGGCUGGGCUCGUGACCUGGAGCAAGGGGUGUGGAGUGAGAGGCAUUGAGAAAGCAGACACAGGAGGGCAUUCCAUGGCAAAUCUCUGCCUUAGUUCCCUUAACUUUCCUUUGCUUCUGCCAACAAGUUGUUAUUUAUUCCCUGCUUGGGGCUAUUGUUUCCCAUUCCUUUGCCCUUGAGGUGGCCACUGUCCCCUUUCUUUCUGCCACUCCAUUUCCCUCUGUCCUUGUCUUUGCCCUCUCUGUCAAAAUUUGGCUCAAAGUGCCAGAAAGCCAUACCUGAUUCACCCUACCUGGGGCACCCCCUCCUUUGCCCAUGUCCUCAGUCCUCUUCCUCAUGGGUGAGCUCUCCUGAAUGAAAGGUGAGAUUAUGGGUCCUUGGAAGAUAUUUUGCAUGUGUCUGCGGGUGGCACCUGCUUUCCCCAACAAUACAAACCAUCAGGCCUCCCGGCGGCAAAGUCAGCCUAGUCCUCAUUCUUCAUAUGGAUAAGUAAUUACUAUGCAAUUAGAAAACACAGAAAAUGAAGGGGCCCUUUGUUCCUGGUUGCUUAUUAAUAUUAAUUUUUUUAAAAAGGUCUCCCUUCCCAGCUUGGGAUCCUACAGAACAGGAAGCAGACAAAUAAUGCCUUUGAACAGCUGUGAUGGGCUGUUGAAAUUAGAUCUGUCAGGGGAUGAGAACACCACGAUGGCAGCCACUCCGUGGUAUAGGCUAAGAGGGUUCCAGGGGAAGGUAUCUUGUAAGUGGUCAAUAGAAUGCUAGAGACACAUCCUAGUCAAUUUGAAUACAAUAAUGAUAAUAGAUGUUAAUAAUAAUAGCUCACAUGUAUUAUGAGUGAGCCAAGUACCAUGUCAAGCCCACCUGCCUUAUCCCAUUAAAUUCUCAUAACCCUAUGAAGUGAGCACUGUCAUUCUCAUUCCCAUUUUAAAGAUUUAAAAACUGUAGUUUGGAAAGGAUAGUAGCUUAUCUGAAGUGGCAGAGACAGGAUUUGAGCCUAAGCCUGUCGUCAUUCUGUCCUCUAAGCCACUGUCAGCGGACGCUCCAUCGUACCAGCCCUGGGAUGGCUGAGCCAGGCUCUGCAACCUUAAAACAGACACUCAAGAAAAAACCACAGCUGCUCUUAACUAAAUUCUCCAUUAUCCUUGGGGGAGGAGAUAACCCCAAAUCAUUUACGAGUGGCCUCAGGAGGCGGUAUAAGUAUUUUUUGCACCUGCUCCUGCUGUUGCAGACACUGCCUGGCUUUGGCUGACAGGUUUCUGGUCCCUGAAUGCACUCAGACCAAUGUCAGACAAAGGAGGCCGGGAGGAGGCGUGGUCGUGUAAGAGGAAGCCAGCCUGAAGAGAAUUAUUGGAAGGGAACCUUUAGCUGAAACAAGGCUGAGGGAAGUUAGCCAAUGCCCAGAAGAAACUAGGCGAUGGAGCACGGGCGGGCUUCUCUGGGAAGACAGACGUCCUCUGUAGGGAUGAGUCAACAUUUUUUCCUGUGGGCUGCGAGGACCGCUUCUGGAAGGUCGCUGGGAAGCCCCGCCCGGCCUUAGGGCUGGGAGGGGAUUGGCUGCCCAGUUGCUGGGGCUUUGCUCUGAGCCAGUGGCGGGGUGGAGGGGCGGGGCCAAGGCGGGAGCAGCGGGCUUCUUGGCCAAUCAUCCUGCAGGGAGGCUGGGCACCCGGUACCAUGGCAACCGCGAGCAGGGCCUCAUUUGUUUUGUAGAUGAGUAAUUACUACACAAUUAGAGAAAGCUAAAAAUAAAGGGGCCCUUUGUUCCUGGUUACUUAUUAAUAUUAAUAAAAUGGUCUGCCCAGGUCUGUGGUAAACAUUUGAUGCCUGCGUGCCUGUGGCAGAGGCUUGUGUAGCCGGGAAAGGCACCCCAGCCCCGCUCGCCCCUCUUUCGGGAAGUUAUUUCUGACUAUAUCCUGGAGAGGGUGGGCUUCUGACCUUGGGGAGAAGAGGAGAGGCUCAGUGUGACAGACAUAGGAUCCAGGAUGUCCUGGAGUCCGGGUCCGUCACUGACUCAGGUGGAAAGGUGGCGGCAGCGUCACCAUCCUUCAGAGAAAAGACAGACACACAGCAGCAAAGCAGACACUAUGGACCGGUGUCAGAGGAAACCCCUAGUCCAGUUUUGCUGUGUCCUUCUGUGUUUUCUGGCUUUUGAUUGAUCAGCUCCAGGUGUGUAAAAUAGUCGUUAAGUCUUCAAUGGAGGUAGCCCCCAAGACUCCAGUGACUCCCCUCCCAUCUGGCUUAAAGGGCACAUUCCGUUCAGGCUUGGAAAUGAUCUGCUGGAGGUUUACACUGUGUUCAGGGUUGUCCCCGUGGCUCCCCAUGCCCUGGCCUUCGAAGUUAAAGCAGCUGAGAGGCUUGCUUUCUAUUCCUUCUCCCUCCUAGGGGGAGAGGUUGCCUUGUUGAUUACUCCAGUGAGGAUGAUUAACAGCUUAAAAAAAAAAAUAGAGGCAGCAUAAGAGCAUAGAAGGCAGAGUAGGGAAUCAGAAGACUUGGUUCCAGGCCUGCUUCCACCUCUACUAAACGAGGAAUUCAGACUAAAGGGUCCUUGGGAGCCAUUUCAGCUCUACAGCUCUGUUUUGCUGCUGUUUCCAAAGCUGGAAAUCCCUUUUCCUUGGAGAUAGGAACAGGGACAGUGACAGUGCCUUAAGAUCUGAGAGAACAGGCCGGGCACGGUGACUCACGCCUGUAAUCCCAGCACUUUGGGAGGCCGAGGCGGCUGAUCACUUGAGGCCAGGAGUUUGAGACCAGCCUGGCCAACAUGGUGAAACCCCAUCUCUACUAAAAAUACAAAAAUCAGCCAGGUGUGGCGGUGUGUGCCUGUAGUCUCAGCUACUGGGGAGACUGAGGCAGGAGAAUUACUUGAACCCGGGAGGCCCAGGUUGCAGUGAGCUGAGAGUGCGCCACUGCACUCCAGCCUGGGUGACAUAGCAAGACUCCCUCUCAAAAAAGGGGAAAAAAAAAGAAAAAAGAUCUGAGAGAAGUGAGUGGAGAGAAAGCCAAGAGGUUCCAGGUGAUAGGAAACUUCGUGGGAAUUUGAAAACAGCCAUGAAUUGUUUAAUGCAUGAAGGCAAUGGGAGGGACAGAAGCGGUUCCAGAACUGUGUAUCAUUUUACACAUCUGUCCUCAGACUUCCAUCCUUGGGUGUGGUUGAUUAAAUCUCUUAGGGUUUGAUUCUGUGUGGAUGGUAUUCAUGAAUAAUAGUGGACCUGUUAAUAGCUGCUGUCAAUGAGCAAAUCAACCCAGAGAUUGUGGCCAGUUCAGUGGCUCUUGAACUUUGCUGCUGUUCCUAAUAGGAACUUUGAUCCUGUUAGGAUCACCUGGGGAGUUUUUAAACUGUGCAGUGGCCAGGCUGCAUCACAGACCCAUCAAACCAGAAUCUAGCAGGGUGAGCCUCAGGCAGGCCCAGUGUGUAACACGGGGCUCAAGUAUCAUCAUGUUCUUGCUGGAUGUAAAGCUCCAUAACAUCUUUGUGGCUGUCACUGGUACCCCAGCCUCCUCUAACUGGGAGGUGGGGAGGUGGGGCUGGGAUCUCUAGCCUGCUGCUGUGGAGCCCACGGCUCUCCAGCCUCCAUUAGUCUUCCCAGCAGGGUCAGGAAGGCCACCCUCCAGGGUGGACCAAGGGGUUUUUGUCCUCAUAGAGGGACCCUCCUGUCUCUCUCGAGGACAGGCCAGUCCUGGCUGAGAUUAAGGGCAUGUACCAGUAGAACUAGCAGCCUGCAGCAACUGUAAACAGAGAAGCAGCCGCCCUCCUUGACUGACCAAUGGGAGCCUUUUGGUAAGGUCGGAGUUUGUUUGUUAUUAAAGACCUAAUUAGAAACAUGAGAGGGAGCUGAAUGGCUCUGUGCUUGGCUAAUUAGUGACAUGUAUGCGCCUGCUUUGAACUUCAAGGACACAGAACUAUUAGUGCUUACAUCAAAAAUGGAUUAAACUCCUGUGCUUUUAUAAUUAUUAAAAAGGAGCUACUCAAGUGGAAAGUCUUUUGUGUGGGUCCUCAAGGGGCUGCCCCUGGGAUAACUUCCCCACCCCACCCUGCCCCCUGCCUGCUAGAGCCCCAGCAGUGAGUUUUCUAUUAGAUAUGAUUGGGCAGUAAAUACCGUUCAGCCCUAGGGUGUGCCAGCUCCCAAAAGGACUUGGCUCUCAGCAGAAUGGAGUGGUCUUUUAGGACUGAGAUCAGCUCUCUGGGUGGCCCCCUGGGUCCAGGCACUUUCCUGGGGUGGGGGAGGGGAGUUCUAGCGAGGGCCCAGGGUUAACCAGGGCUUACUUUCCCUCUGGCAGUGCCCUCUCUGCUUCCACGCUGACCCCACCAGUACUGCAAGUCUGCUUAUUCUUUGGGCUGUGGCGUAGUGGAGGGUGGCCUAGUCCUCAGGAGAGAGGCAGUCCUGUAUCUCUUGGGGCAGUCAGAUCCUGACCUCAGGGAACCCCCACCGUGAUGGAAGAGAUGUUUCCACUGCCAGGGAGCUCCCAAUUUGGAAAGGCAACAGGGUCCAAGCCCUUAGGAGCUUCUACUCCAAGGCUGGAGAAUCUAUUCUGUGUCCUUGAAUUUGCAGUUUCUCUGGGGCAAAGAAAGAUCCAAGUAAACAGAGGAAACCUUGUCAAAGUGUGAUUCCAGAAGGGACAACUGAGCAGCAUGAUUUAAAAAGCAUGUGCCUUCAAGUUAGAGCCAGAUUUGGUCCUGUCUGAGACACUGUGUGGCAUUGGACACAUUUCCUAGCUGUUCAAACCCUUGGUCUUCUUAUCUGUAACAGGGGUUACACAGCUGCUCUUACAAGAUGUUCGGAGCAUGAAAAAAGAUCGUGUGAAACACCUACCAACAUGCCUGGCAACACAGUAGGGGCUCAUAAGUAUGAGUUCCCUUUCCAGCCUCACACCUGCAGAAGCUACAGCUUCUAGAACUUUGUGCUUCUUGCCUCAUUGGUUUUCACCUCCAGGCCCUGUUUUGUCCCUACCAGUAUCAGGCCUAACAGGGGCAGAGUGAUAUCUAAUUCUUACAUAGCUUUUCAUCAUGAUUGAGAAGACUACAUUAGGCUGCCUCGUAAGUCUGUGGUCCCAGCCUUGGAUUUCACAGUGUUUUCUUUUAGCAGCAGUCUGUCAUGCAGAAACUGGGCCUGCAGUGAGUGCAAUCACUUAUAAGACACAAGCAAGGAUCUGAGCCUCCUGGCAGGUAGCAGGCAGGGAGGUAGCUUUCAGGUUGGGAAUUGGUGCCUGAGCACACCACAGAGCAGCAACAUGAGAGGGUGGCUGGCGACAUGUGGGGAAAAGCCAAACUGACUUCUUUUUUGAAAAAAAGAGACGAGUGUGCUUCAAAGACAGAGGCAGUCAAUGGAUCAAAGCAAAGCAAGGGACAUUUUCAGGACUGAACUAGGAGAAACUUGGAGCCACCAAACUGUAAGAGACAGUAGGGAGUUGUCUCCGGGCAGCAAGCUCCCUGUCUAUUUCCUGUGGAGUCUCAGACCUGGGAGGGCUGGAUGAGGAAGCAAAGGCUCUGGUAUCACCCAACAGGGGCCACCUCUCUGCCUUUUCUCUGCUGAGUGGUGAUGGUGGCAUCUCGCCUCCCCAGGGCUGCGUGCCCAGCUGCUGGGUGGUUCAAUGCAGCAUGGCAUGGGUGCUGCAGGUUCCGGGGAGCCUCCUUGUCUGUUAUUCCUUGCAAAUUCUAACCUGUGUGGGCCUGGAGUCUGAAGCCAAUUAAUUUAAGGAAGAGGCAGCAGGAUGUUAGUGUUAAAACACCGCCUGCUUCAGCCAAACCAUAAACAUUUGUCUCCCGGGUUGGUUUUCCCUCCUCUUCUGAAGCGCUUUAGAGACUCAGGGUAAGGUGUUGUUGAAGCAUCCGUUCACGGUGGAGAGGGAUCAGGAACACCAUCCUGCGUUUGAGACUCGAAGCCUGGUCUGGUGAAGCCUGGCAGAUAGUUCACACAAGCAGGACAAGCCCCGUGCCAAUGCCAGGCAGGAGUGAUAUCCAGUCACCGCACAGGGCCCCAGUGACUGCCUCAUGGCCUUUCCCUUCCCGGGGCCCUCCGCACUUGCCUCCUGGAAACCUGCAAACAAGCCCAGUCCCUCAGGGCCCUUGGGGGUUGAGAGAAAUGAGAACUGACCUCGGCUCCAGAAAGUUCUUUCCUUGGCCUCAUGACAAAAGCCUGGUUUCUCUGGCCACAAGGCCACAGCCCAUUCAAGGCUGCUCCAUCCCCAGAAUUUACACCAUGAGCAGACAGCAGUCAACUGCUAACCACCAUCCUCCCUCACCCACCUUCCCAACCCGCCAGUCCAGAACCCACCCAGCCUGGCCUUGGGGCUUGAGAUACACUUACAGACUCAGAUCAGGGCUGAUAAUAAAAACACACCAGGAGGGCCAGGCACAGUGGCUCAGGCCUGUAAUCCCAGCACUUUGGGAGGCUGAGGCGGGUGGAUCACCUGAGGUCAGGAGUUCGAGACCAACCUGGCCAACAUGGUGAAACCCUGUCUCUACUAAAAAUACAAAAAUUAGCCAGAUUUGAUGCCGCACACCUGUAAUCCCAGGUACUCAGAAGGCUGAGGCAGGAAAACCACUUGAACCCAGGAGGCAGAGGUUGCAGUGAGUCGAGAUUACACCACUGCACUGUUGAGAUUAUAUCUCAACAGCAAAUGCAUGGUCCUAGCCACAAAGCCUUUCUCAGGUCGGUUCUGGGUGUUUGGAACUUUUUCCUUACACCAAUCCGAAUGGUAGUGUGCUUCCCCAGCUUUACCACUGACAUGUUAUAUGAGAGUUUUAGAACUGGCUAAUAGUGAUAUUAUCUCCUGAGGGUUUUGGGGGAGUGUGACUUGACCAGAAGCCAAGAUCUUUCUACAAAAUAAUUCACAAGUGUUAAGUGCUAAUGUCCAUCAGUUCCCUACUUGAGACAGGCCAACAUUAACCAGUAGACAUUAUCAGCACCAACCUCAGUGGUCUGAAUCAGGUUAAGUUUUGAGAACAAGCAGAAACUACAACUUAUCAUAAGACUGGCGCCAUUGUCACUGACAUUUGGAAUGUCUGUGUGAUGCUGGCUGCCCUGUCAGCCCAGUGCAUGCACAGACAACUCACCAUGUGUCCCGUGCAGUGUGUAAGAGGAGCCAGGGGACUCCAGAUACAUCAAGACUAGCAUGAUGUUGACACCAGGCUGCGUUUGUACCUCUCAGUAAUAUAUCUGUUUGUAUAUGCAGACAGUGAAAAAGAAAUCCCAUCACAUUGCUCUCUUAAUCCUCCCCCAGUUUUAAAGUAUUUUCCCCCUUCCCUUCUGAAAUAGCCUGAAUUUCAGCAGAGCUUUAAAAACUACAUUGUGUAUAAAAUUGAUUGUCCCUGCAUCUGGGUCCCUGAACUGAUUUGAUUUUAACUUAGCAUGUCAUACAAUUUUCCCAGGUUGGACAUCAUUGCCGAUCUUCUCUACCAGUCUCUCCUACCUCCAGGCUAAGCUCUAGAAGGAAAGCUUGAGCCAAGGAUUGCUGGGACAUAGCUGGCCGGGCAGACUCCUGAAGUAUAAUCCUACCUUGCUCUGCUCAAGACAUGCCAAUUCAUAACCGAGUAUUCUCCUUCCAUUAUCAGAAAUAGAUUUUGUCUUUUCAUGCUGACCUUUCCCAUUUGACCAUCUGCAAUUAUUUACAGUGGGCACUGCUUUCAGAGGACACAUGAAGGAAACUGCAGAAUGGGGUCCCCAAUUCUGUUCCCCAGGAAGGCCUUUGGCUGCCCAGUUGCUGAAAUUCAGAGCCCUCCAGUAAAGAGUGGCUGGCUGUUCAGAGGGACUGAUGCAGGCCCUCACUGUUGACAGCCAACUGGCAUUGUGGACCCAGUGUCCACUGAGGAAUGGCAGAAAGUUGCUCUUACUCUUUGGAGAAUAUGCCCUCUGACUAGGAACAUAGAGUUCCCUGAGAGCCCUGAGAGUUCCCCAACUGCCUGGAGGAGUUUCUUGCUAAUAGGGGAGACAGAGUCCUACGACUAUGGAGUUUUAAAUCAAGGCAGAUAUAAGCAUGAUAUAGACAAGAUGAAGGUAGAGGUGUGUGUUGGAGAGUGUGAUAACUUUAUUUAGUUUCUUUAAAUUUCUCUGAAACAAAAACUCCUAAAAUUCAGUGUGAUGGAUUAACACAGCCUCUGCCCUCAUAGAUUAUCACACAGGCUAUGACCUCUCCUGCUCUCAGUCCUCCGUCCUUUCGGGACUAGGGGUUGGGAAUGGAGGCCGUGACACCAGUCAGCCCAAAUCCCUUCUGAAUUGGACUUGGCAAAGGUGGGCCCUCCAUUGCAUUUGCCUCCCCGAGCCACACGCACAGGCUGGGCAGGGAAGAGUCUCUCUCCCGGAAAUGUACCAGGGGCCACUGCGGUCUUCUGCCUGAAAUGAAACCUGGCAGCAGCAGA